AGUGAGGGGUCCCACACGCCUGGAGCCGAGGGUCUGUGUCAAGAGCGGCAGGGGCUGCAGGAGAUAAGAGAAACGGGUGAGGGCGCCGCGCGGGGCUGGACUGGGAAGAGAACGCUGGGCGGACGGAGGGGGCGGAAGGAAAACUAAGGGGUCUGCAGGGAUCGAAGAGCCUUGGGGCCUGCGCUAGGGCGGGAGCGGCGCGGGCUGGAAGGAGAGCACUCCUUCCUGUGUGCCCUGGGGCUCCUUUAGUGUGCGGGAGCCUACGCUGGAACUCGCCCACCACCCACUGCUGCGAGCUCUCACCCUGCCGAGGAGCUCAGUCUGGCUGCCGUGGGGUGUGUGUAGGCUUCAGAGACAUGGGAUCACGGAAGACUGAAGCAGAAACAGUGGAUUAAGACUUCCUGAGCGAUAGCUGGCACUGCCUUCCCCACAAUGGCAGAGGUGGUGGCUGAGGUGGCCGAGAUGCCAACACAGAUGUCACCAGGGGCAGUGGAGAUGUCAACACCUAUGUCGGCAGAGAUGAUGGAGAUGUCAACAGAAGUGACUGAGAUGACACCUGGGGAGGCCCUUGCCUCAUCCCUCUUCUUCCAGCAUCACCAGUUCAUGUGCUCUGAGUGUGGCAGCCUCUAUAACACACUGGAGGAAGUCCUCUCACACCAGGAGCAGCACAUGCUUGCUGUCUCAGAGGAGGAGGCACUGACCACACAGAAUGUUGGCCUGGAGCCGGAGCUGGUGCCGGGUGCUGAGGGGCCCUUCCAGUGUGGUGAAUGCAGCCAGCUCAUCCUCUCCCCUGGGGAGCUCCUGGCCCACCAGGAUGCCCACCUCCGAGAGUCUGCAAACCAGAUCCAAUACCAGUGCUGGGACUGCCAGGAGCUGUUCCCCUCGCCCGAGCUGUGGGUGGCUCAUCGAAAGGCCCAGCACCUUUCUGCUACGGUAGCUGAGCCACCAGUGCCACCUCCUUUGCCUCCCCCAACACCACUGCCUCCACCUUCUCCCCCAUCCGAAGUCAAGAUGGAGCCCUAUGAGUGUCCUGAGUGCUCUACCCUCUGCGCCACCCCUGAGGAGUUCUUGGAGCAUCAGGGCACCCACUUUGACUCCCUAGAGAAAGAGGAGCGCAAUGGGUUGGAGGAGGAGGAAGAGGACGAUGAGGAGGAUGAAGAAGAUGAUGAAGAGAUGGAGGAUGAGGAGGCCAUGGCAGAGGUCGGUGAUGAUGCUGUGGGAGGUGACGAGUCCACAGCUGGCUGGGCUCAGGGCUGCGGGGACUGUCCCCAGCACCAGCCCUCAGCAGGGGCUCGCCGGCAACACCGGCGGACGGCUCACAGCCCGGCAUCUGCCACCCACCCCUUCCACUGCAGCCAGUGUCAGCGCAGUUUCAGCUCCGCCAACCGGCUGCAGGCUCAUGGGCGGGCCCAUGUUGGUGGCACACAUGAGUGUACAACCUGCUCCAAGGUCUUCAAGAAAGCAGCAUCGCUUGAGCAGCACUUGCGGCUGCAUCGCGGGGAAGCCCGCUACCUCUGUGUAGACUGUGGCCGCGGCUUUGGCACAGAACUCACGUUGGUGGCUCACCGGCGGGCCCACACUGCCAACCCAUUGCAUCGCUGUCGUUGCGGCAAGACGUUCAGCAACAUGACCAAGUUCCUCUACCACCGGCGCACUCACGCCGGCAAAAGCGGGGCACCUCCCACAGGAGCAACAGCUCCCCCAGCUCCAGCGGAGCCCACCCCUCCACCACCACCCCCUGCCCCACCUGCCCAGCUGCCCUGCCCACAGUGCUCCAAGUCCUUUGCCUCAGCUUCCCGGCUGUCCCGGCACCGGCGUGCAGUACACGGGCCCCCUGAACGGCGUCACCGCUGUGGGGUUUGUGGCAAGGGCUUCAAGAAGCUGAUCCACGUGCGCAACCACCUGCGGACACACACGGGUGAGAGGCCCUUCCAGUGCCACUCAUGUGGCAAGACCUUUGCUUCUUUGGCCAACCUCAGCCGCCACCAGCUGACCCAUACGGGUGCACGUCCCUACCAAUGCCUGGACUGUGGCAAGCGCUUCACACAGAGCUCCAACCUGCAGCAGCACCGGCGGUUGCACUUGCGGCCAGUCGCCUUUGCCCGCGCCCCCCGCCUCCCCAUCACUGGUCUCUACAACAAGAGUCCCUACUACUGCGGGACUUGUGGCCGCUGGUUCCGCGCCAUGGCGGGCUUGCGACUGCAUCAGCGGGUCCAUGCCCGAGCUCGGACUUUGACGCUACAGCCUCCCAGAUCACCAUCUCCUGCCCCACCCCCACCUCCAGAGCCUCAACAGACUAUCAUGUGCACAGAGCUGGGGGAGACCAUCGCCAUCAUUGAGACAUCCCAGCCACUGGCGCUUGAGGACACCCUGCAGCUGUGCCAGGCUGCACUGGGGGCCAGUGAAGCAGGCGGGCUCUUGCAGUUGGACACGGCCUUCGUGUGACGCAGCUGAAAAGCAACAACAAAAGGGUUUGGUUGCAACAGCCAGUGUGGGUACCUCUGGGGAGAGAGGACCUCCUCUGACAAACUGGUCUGGUACCCACCAUGUGCCAGGAUCCACCCUGGCCUCUUUUUACCCACUGACUCCCCAGAACAACCCUUCCAGGCUUCUCUUGUCAUCUUUCUCUGCCUGAGGGGAAACUGAAGCUCUGAAAUGCGAUGUGAUCUGUACCAGGUCACCCAGCUAUGCUGCAAAGUGGGUUGGCCAAGGCCCUUUGCACUGCAUCACCCUGGUGCCCAGCAACAUCAGGUAACCUUCACUGAGCACCAAGCUUAUGCCAGGUCUGUGCUGGCCACUCUCAUAUACCUCUUCAGAUCCUCUGCUUGUACCCCCAGCCCUUGCCUUCCCUGGAUUUUGGGCACCCAGGACUUUGCUCUGCCUGGUGGAGGGUACUUGAUUUCUCUGGGCUUCCUUCAUCUCAAUUCUGACAGUGUGGAAGGAAAUCUGUAGGUACCCAGGUCCUCAGCUCCAGACUGGGUGAUGCUGGAGACCCAGGAGCAAGUCAGCACAGGCUCUGCCCACAGGAGGCAUGCACAAUCUGGUAGGAGAAACGCACAAGUACAGAUAGCUUGCUCUCUGAGUGUGUCUCAUUGAUUCAUUCAGCCUGUGUGUCCUAAAGCCUCCCUUCUCCCAUACUGGGUGAUGCUGGGGGCAGAGAUGAGUCAGGCCUAAGGCUUCUCUGGGCUGUGAUGGGGAUGUGCAGGGACAGUGGGAUCCCAGGAAACAGACCUCCAUGGUGGGAGAUCAGGAGUUAAGGACUUCCUAGAGAAGGUAGUCCCUGAAGGAAAAGUAGGAAUCUGGCAGUGAAAGAGGAAAAGAACAUUCCAGGCAGACAGCACUGCAAGAGGGUGAGCUCUUGGUGUAUUUGGAGACCAUCCAGUUAUUCAUCUGACUGCCUACCUGAGGCAAGCACCACACUUACCACUGUAUGUGUACUAUGAUCCCAACAGGCUUGUGACAUAGAUUUCAUAUUAUCCCUGUUGUAUAGAUUUUUAAAACUGGUGGCUGGGCGUGGUGGCUCACGCCUGUAAUCCCAGCACUUUGGGAGGCCGAGGCGGGCAGAUCACGAGGUCAGGAGAUCGAGACCAUCCUGGCUAACACGGUGAAACCCCGUCUCUACUAAAAAUACAAAAAAUUAGCCAGGAGUGGUGGCGGGCGCCUGUGGUGGCCAGCUACUCAGGAGGCUGAGGCAGGAGAAUGGCGUGAACCCGGGAGGCGGAGCUUGCAGUGAGCCGAGAUCGCGCCACUGCACUCCAGCCUGGGCGACAGAGUGAGACUCCCUCUCAAAAGAAAAUAAAAAUAAAAAUAAACUGGCCAGGUGCGGUGGCUCACGCUUGCAAUCCCAGUGCUUUGGGAGACUGAGGCAGGAGGAUCACUUAAGGCCAGGAGUUCGAGACCAGCCUGGGCAACAGCAAGACCUCAUCUCUACAAAACUUAAAAGUUAGCCAGGCCUGGUGGCACAUGCCUGUAAUCCGAGUGCUUUGGGAGGCUGAGGCAGGAGGAUCACUCGAGCUCAAGAAUUCAAGACCUGGGCAAGAGAGAGAGACUUUGUCUCUAUUAAAAAUAAAAAUGAUUGGCCGAGCAUGGUGGUGCACACCAGUAUUCCCAGCUACUCUGGAGGCUGAGGCGGAGGCAGGAUUGCUUGAUAUGAGGGAGAUUGAGGCUGCAGUGAGCUGUGUUCACACCACUGCACUCCAGUCUGGGCAACAGUGCAAGACCCUGUCACUU